ACUCGAUCAGCCCGCCGGCUCCGGAGCGGCUCUGCCUUCCCGAGCGCGGGACGCGGCGCCCUGGGGGAGGAGGGCGAAGCGACGCGGCGAUGGCUCCGCGGGCACUCCCGGGGUCCGCCGUCCUAGCCGCUGCUGUCUUCGUGGGAGGCGCCGUGAGUUCGCCGCUGGUGGCUCCGGACAAUGGGAGCAGCCGCACAUUGCACUCCAGAACAGAGACGACCCCGUCGCCCAGCAACGAUACUGGGAAUGGACACCCAGAAUAUAUUGCAUACGCGCUUGUCCCUGUGUUCUUUAUCAUGGGUCUCUUUGGCGUCCUCAUUUGCCACCUGCUUAAGAAGAAAGGCUAUCGUUGUACAACAGAAGCAGAGCAAGAUAUCGAAGAGGAAAAGGUUGAAAAGAUAGAAUUGAAUGACAGUGUGAAUGAAAACAGUGACACUGUUGGGCAAAUCGUCCACUACAUCAUGAAAAAUGAAGCGAAUGCUGAUGUCUUAAAGGCGAUGGUAGCAGAUAACAGCCUGUAUGAUCCUGAAAGCCCCGUGACCCCCAGCACACCAGGGAGCCCGCCAGUGAGUCCUGGGCCUUUGUCACCAGGGGGGACGCCAGGGAAGCACGUCUGUGGCCAUCAUCUGCAUACGGUGGGCGGUGUUGUCGAGAGGGAUGUGUGUCAUCGGUGUAGGCACAAGCGGUGGCACUUUAUAAAGCCCACUAACAAGUCCAGAGAGAGCAGACCACGGCGCCAAGGCGAGGUCACGGUCCUUUCUGUUGGCAGAUUUAGAGUUACAAAAGUGGAGCACAAGUCAAACCAGAAGGAACGGAGAAGCCUGAUGUCUGUUAGUGGGGCUGAAACCGUCAAUGGGGAGGUGCCGGCAACACCUGUGAAGAGAGAACGCAGUGGCACAGAGUAGCAGCAAUGACUUGACUUGAAGAGCUCUAAGAGACUGAAAACUUAUAUGAAGUUGCCUUGGGAAUAUUUUUAUAUAUUUUAUACAGUUUCUAUCAUGGAGUCAGCAGGCACGUGGAUAAAACCUAAAAGGGAAUAUUAUUGCUGUGCCAUAUACAGAAUUCAGUUUGCUUUGAAACAAGUUUUGGUUGAAAGAGUCUGUUGAAAAUUUUAUUAUACUUCCAGGGAAGGAAAGAGCUGUUUUUAUCUUCUUAACCACUCCCAGCCUCUACUCUUCCCAGCCCCUAAUCCCAGGCCUUGGUGUACACACUGUAGUUUUUCCAUUAUGAUGAGUAUGUGCAGUGAUACUAUUCAUGUACAGUCUGAGCUUAUGCUCAGGGGUGUGUGUGUAUAUGUGUAUGCAUGUGUGCACGUGAGUGUGUGUUUCUUUUUCCAGUUCCUGCAUCCUAUUUUGACACUGGUUGUAAGAAGAUCUUGAUACAUACAGGUUAGCUGUUACAAAAGAUAAAAGAUGAAUCUUCAGUGGUAAAAGCUCAGUGGAAAUAAUCUAGUUAGCCCUGAGGAGUUGAUUCCCCAAGGGACCAUGGAGUCAGAUGGGACCAGAUGCUAGACUUUGGAUUCCUUGACCACAAAUUCAGCAUUAACUCCUGCCACCACCAUGUCACUCCUACAGCACUUACACAUUUUGAGAAGGUUUUUUUUUUUUUUUUUUUGAGGCAGAGUCUCGCUGUGUCCCCUAGGCUGGAGUGCAGUGGCACAAUCUCCACUCACCUCAAUCUCCACCUCCCCAGGUUCAAGCGAUUCUCCUGCCUCAGCCUCCCAAGUAGCUGGGAUUACAGGCAUGCACCACCACGCUCGACUAAUUUUUGUAUUUUUAGUAGAGACGGGGUAUCACUAUAUUGGUCAGGCUGGUCUUGAACUCCUGACCUCAGGCGAUCUACCCGCCUCGGCCUCCCAAAGUGCUGGGAAUAUAGGCGUGGGCCACUGCACCCGGUUUUUUGUUUUUUUUUGUUUUUUUUUUUUUUUUAACCUUUAGCUGAGCGAUUCUUGGUUAAUCCAUUGAAUAAAGGAGAAAAUGGUUGAAAGUCACACACACACAAAUUUGUUUGGACAACCCAAGGCCAAAACAAAAGAACCCUGCUUCUCUCUUUUUUUUUUUUUUUUUUUUUUUUUGAGGCGGAGUCUCGCUCUGUCGCCCAGGCUGGAGUGCAGUGGCACGAUCUCAGCUCACUGCAAGCUCCACCUUCUGAGUUCACGCCAUUCUCCUGCCUCAGCCUCCUGAGUAGCUGGGACUACAGGUGCCCACCACCACGCUUGGCUUAUUUUUUUUGUAUUUUUAGGAGAGACGGGGUUUCACCGCAUUAGCGAAGAUGGUCUCGAUCUCCUGACCUCGUGAUCCACCCGCCUCGGCCUCCCAAAGUUCUGGGAUUACAGGCUUGAGCCACUGCGCCCGGCCUAGAACCCUGCUUCUCAUAUAAGAUGGGCCUGCACCUACCUCUGGCAUGUUUUUCUUUGUGUAUUUCCUGUUUUUCAUCCUGUAACUAAUGCUCAUUAUUUAAAACACUCCAGUUACUUUUCCCUUUAGGCCUGGCAAACUUUUCUUUUUCUUUUUUUUUUUUAUAACUGUACAUUUUACAAAACACCUGAAAGGACCCAGAGGCAUAAAUAGUAUUACAUGAUUUAUGGUAGCUCUGGGGUGAGCUGUGGGGGAGGCCAGUUACAAGGUCUCCAAGACCCGCCUCCAUGUCAGUGUUGGGGGGUGCCUUGAGCACUUCUUUUAUUUCAUAUAGGAAAAUGCACAUCUUUCAUUUGUCUCCCAAAAGAUGAUUUCCAUAAAAAUAUACUUCAAAGUAUUUACUGUACAUAGACUUCAAUGAUUUUAUUUCCAGCAUCAAACUAAACAUUUCUAACCUUUUAAAUAAAUGGGGAAUUUAGUUUCAUGAGAAUUUUUACUGACAACUAAUAAACACUGUAUGUGUACAUAUUCAUAUACACUGUGGACUGGAGAAAGUCAGUAUGGAAAUAAAUUUCACUGAGAUCCAGAAAGUAGCAAUAUAGGACUUUUAGGGGUAUGUAUUAGUGUAAAUAAUAUAUGUGCAGUCUAGGCUAAUCAUUUUAAUUAAAAACAAAUAAGCAUACUUUUUUGCUUUAAAAAUAUGCCCUCAAAAUGGUGGGGGAUAAAAUGUAAGAUAUUCUUUAGCUUUAAUUAUUUUUCCAUCUUAUUCAAGUCAGAGCACUUUUUUUUAAAUAGCAAUACAACAGGCAAGAGAAUACUCAAAAAUAUUUAAAACUGUAUUGAUACCAAGAGUAUGUUUUAAAUAUUUUCUAAUAAAUACUUGAGCGGUUUUUGUCUGGCAGGCUUCCAAAUUUGCCAAAAUUAAGCGUUCAGUAUUUUCAACACAUACGCUUUUUACUGGUUUAUACUGAACUAUCUGAUGAGAAUUCCUGUGUUCCCAAAGCAACUGAUGUUUACAGGUCUUGUGUUACUCCUCCUCCUUUCUAAGGAUGAGGGAAUCCACAACAGACUUUCUCUAGAAAACACUAAUGAUGGACAACUUUUUGGUGUCAUCAAUGAGUUGGCUACUACCUUGAUGUAAAAAUUUGUAAGGAAAAUUUUCACCAUUUCGAGUGUCAAGUGUAUUUUUAACUGUCUGGUUUGUACUUUUAUGACUUUUGUACUACCAAAGCGGAGUUAAAAAUAAAAAUGUUAAACGCA